CUAAGAGGGAGUUUUGCUUUAAACUUAAUUCUGUGUUCACGGUUGCUGUUGUCACUCCAUGUAGCCGUUAUGGGUAAUUUGCAAGGCUUUAUGUUUUUAAAAUCUCACCAUAUACCCUAGGUAUGUCACUUCAUGCCUGUUUUUAAGAAAAGAAAAAAUUUAAAAAGCACUCACCAGCAUCCCUGUCUCUGUACCUGUUAAGUGGAGCUUCGUCUUAGCUGCUUUUGCUCAUUAACUGGUGUCUCAUAUAAACAUAGUAUAAGAUUGAAUGAAUCAUUUUGACAUCUCAUCGGUUGAACUUAGUUACAGUGGCAAAGUUGUAGAACAGUCUUAAAACUUAUUUAACGAAUGUUAAUUGUUGACUAGCGCUGCGGAUUGUAAGUGAUUGAAUACUAAAAUUGAUCUUUUCCUAAUAAUAAACAUGUUGAACACUUCGUAAAGCUUCAUAAAGUGCGUAUUUGCAAGAGGCCUCCUAACUCUUGCUCCUUCCGUCCACAGUCAGUUUCCAUCUGGCAGCUAGAAUGAGCUUUUCAAUAACAUGAAUUUGGCUUAUUCCCCUCCUGAGUCACUUCCAUUUGCUGCUCUGCGGGGUCGGGUGCCUGCCUCCCUUGGUAAUUGCAUCUCACACAGUUUUUUCCCUUUUGUUCCCAGUGCCCCUCGCUGCCUUGUGUUCUUUGACAUUGGAAAGAAGGUCUCGUUAAGGAUCUCUGUAUGUUCCUUUUGCCCUGUGUGCACUUCCUUUGGAUCCUUGCAAUUAUCUUUCUCCUUCUAAGGUUGUUAUUUCAAAGAGUACUUGCACAUCCCUUCUCUUGUAAAGAACCACUCUUCCACCUGCCUCCCUCUUCAGCCUGAGAUACGUUGUCAAUCUCAUCCUGAAACUCAACAGUGUAAAUUUGAUGGCCAGGAGACAAAAGGAUCCAAGUUCAUUACCUCCAGUGCGAGUGACUUCAGUGACCCGGUUUACAAAGAGAUUGCCAUUACGAAUGGCUGUAUUAAUAGAAUGAGUAAGGAAGAACUCAGAGCUAAGCUUUCAGAAUUCAAGCUUGAAACUAGAGGAGUAAAGGAUGUUCUAAAGAAGAGACUGAAAAACUAUUAUAAGAAGCAGAAGCUGAUGCUGAAAGAGAGCAAUUUUGCUGACAGUUAUUAUGACUACAUUUGUAUUAUUGACUUUGAAGCCACUUGUGAAGAAGGAAACCCACCUGAGUUUGUACAUGAAAUAAUUGAAUUUCCGGUUGUUUUACUGAAUACGCAUACUUUAGAAAUAGAAGACACGUUUCAGCAGUAUGUAAGACCAGAGAUUAACACACAGCUGUCUGAUUUCUGCAUCAGUCUAACUGGAAUUACUCAGGAUCAGGUAGACAGAGCUGAUACCUUCCCUCAGGUACUAAAAAAAGUAAUUGACUGGAUGAAAUUGAAGGAAUUAGGAACAAAGUAUAAAUACUCACUUUUAACAGAUGGUUCUUGGGAUAUGAGUAAGUUCUUGAACAUUCAGUGUCAACUCAGCAGGCUCAAAUACCCUCCUUUUGCGAAAAAGUGGAUCAAUAUUCGGAAGUCAUAUGGAAAUUUUUACAAGGUUCCUAGAAGCCAAACCAAACUGACAAUAAUGCUUGAAAAAUUAGGAAUGGAUUAUGAUGGGCGGCCUCACUGUGGUCUUGAUGACUCUAAGAAUAUCGCCCGAAUAGCAGUUCGAAUGCUUCAGGAUGGGUGUGAACUCCGAAUCAACGAGAAAAUGCAUGCAGGACAGCUAAUGAGUGUGUCCUCUUCCUUACCAAUAGAGGGCACUCCACCACCACAAAUGCCACAUUUUAGAAAGUAACAGUUUUGUGUGUGGAUCAUUCCAAUUGAAGUUGCUAUGAAGAGGUAGCAGAUGAAUCUCAUUGAAUUAGUCCUGUAGUGCAAACUUUAAGCACCUUAAAACAUUUAAAAUCUUAUUACAGGUGAUAGAGAUAGAUACAUGUAUGUGAACAGAUUUUGUAGGAAGGCAUACUGAAUUCUUUGUCACCAGCACUUUUGAUAUGAACAGUAUUCGUUACAUAGUAACAGUUCCUGCUUACAACUGAAUUUUAUAAUUUAAGGUGUUCAAGAUAUAUUCUUUUUGGUUUUAAAAUGCAAAAUCUUAUUGGCUGUUCUGUUGAAUGUCAUAUCUUACUGGUGUUUAAAUAUGUAAUGUGUUUCUUUAUUAACAUCACUAGAUGAAACCAUAUCUUAAAAUGCAGAAAUGAUUGGAAGGUAGAUCUUAUCUAGCCUUUGGAUUUCAAGAAUAUCAUAGUCCUUUUGAUUUUCAAAGUUUAUAUGUGAAGUUCACCAUGUAUGUGGUGAAUUUCGUAAGGUACUUGGUAUACAUAUCUGCCUAUGUUUCUUUUCAACUCAUAAUUGGAAGAAUUAUGAUGGAUUAUAGGGUUUGGUUAAAAAUCCAGUUACUGAAGGAAUUAAUGAAAACGUAGAAGAAAGUACUAAAAGGAAUAUCAUAAGGGCUGUAGCUCAAACUUCAUAAUACAUAAAUCACUGGGGUCUUUUUGGAUUUGGUUGUUUGAUUCGCCUUCCUUUUUUGACAUAUGUAUGCCUUAAUUCUUAAAUCUGAGGGACCAUGCUUUGAAAUAGACUGAAAAUUAAGGGUCACCACCUAAUUUUACUUUGUAUUCAGUAUCGUAAGUGAGGUUAAUAAAGUCAAUACUUUCUACCAUAUAUUACGUUUUUGUUAUUAAAAAACUUCAUUGGCCACUAGUGAAGUUAGUCAAUAAAAGACUUGUUUUUCUGAUUUUACAUAGUAAAUGGCUGCUAAGUAUUGAGUAAUUCUUAACUAAUUCUAAAAACUAAAAUGUGCAUUUCGACUUGAUAAGGUAAAACUCUUAUCUAGAGGCUAAACCCAUGUAUUUUCAGAAUUGAAUUUUUCUCCUUGUAGCUUUCAGGGAACAAUUUCAUUGACAUUGCUUGCUUCCUGCCUUUUACCUUUUAAUAAAAAUUGUGAUGCUACUUUAUUCUAAAGAUUUAUAUUUUAUAACCAGAUGAAUUUCCUCAAAGGUUUCCAAACCUAUAUCAUAUAGGGUGAAAAGCAGGAAAGUAGACAUUUUUCUUGGCGUGGGAAUUCUCUACAUAGGGCAGUAGAUUUCUUAAGCCAAUGAAUUUCUGCUUUUCAGCAGUAGUCAUAUAAUCAGUAUCAUAAAGAAUAAUGUGUAAAUAACAGAAGGCAUAUGAGAGUGUGGUGUUCCUAGAUGAGCUGUUACAGAUUAUAGUAAAAUAAGGAAAUCUAAGUGCUUUAAGUUUAUACAGUUAACUCUUAGGAUAAGAGGGAUGUAUGCUGAGAUGUUUGUGCAUCCCAGAUAGCACUGUACGAUAACCUGUAAAGUAUUACUGAAUACUGAAUAGCUGAAACUGCAAUUGGAAAAUCUGAUGAUGACGAGGAAAUAUUACGUUUCCAGUUUUUUUAGCUCUAUCUGCUAAUUUCUUUGCCUGUUUUCACUUUCGCCAAGUACCAACAAGCUCAUGUUGUAUUUCUUUUUAAGAACUUCAACAUUAUAAGCUCUCAGUACCCUAUUUUGUUGUUGUUGUUGUUUGAGACAGAGUUUUUGCUCGUCUGCCAGGAUGGAGUGCAGUGGUGCGAUCUUGGCUCACUGCAACCUCCGCCUCCUGGGCUCAGGUGAUCCUCUUGCCUCAGCCUCCUGAGUAGCUCAGAUUACAGGCGCGUGCCACCACACCCGCCUAAUUUUUGUAUUUUUGGUAGAGGCGGGGUUUCACCAUGUUGGUCAGGCUGGUCUUGAACUCCUGACCUCAAGUGAUUUGCCCACCUUGACCUCCUACAGACGUGAGCCACUGCGCUCAGCCAUAGAUUUUACUGUCUUAACCCAUUUUAAUUCCUCUGUUGAGUCUCUGUCCUCCCCUCCAAUUUGAUUUGGGAUUUUGCUGAUGAGAUGAUACUAAACAUUGAGAGUACUGCUUUUUACUCUGACUUUUAUUGUGUUGUCUUUGAAAGACAAAUAGUACAACUUUUUACAAGGAAACACGUAAGAGAUGGAUGUCCAUGAAAACAAUAUUAGUAUAUUCUAUUAUUGUUUCUUAUUAAUAGUUACUUAGUAUUUACAAACAAUUUAUUAUUAGCUGUGUUAACUUUUAUUCUAUGCUUCAUAUGCUCUGACAUUGACAUAGUGGAUUUCUGCUGAUUUUUUUCAAAUCCGCAAUCUUUAUAACCAACUGAAGUAUAUAAUAGAGCAUUACAUUUUAUCUUUAUUUGUGUUCUGUUGGAUCAAGUAUUUAACAUUUGCUCUGAAAAAAAUGUUUUUGUGAUGUGUCUUUGUUGCCUUGAGAUAGAUCCAUUUAUCCUGCCUCCUAGGGAGAAGUUUCUGCCUGGAUUGAAACAAAAAAACACAGGUGUCACAAGCAUGUUACCUAUUAAGAGAGAGAGGGUAUCUCUGAAGACUAAUUAAAAUGGUAAUUUUUAAAAAGAUGUGACCAGUUGACUUUUAGUAUAUCAUCCCAAGUAUUAUCCCCAAAAUGAUAAUGCAAAACAGAAUAAUUUGGAGACCAGGAGAAAAACUGGUAUGAUUACUGGGGAGGGGAAGAAGCACAGGUGGUCAAGAUAAUAAUGCAUGUUUGGCCUCAGCUGUAGUUGCCAAAGAAACUACCUGCCUCACAGAUGAGCACGCACGGGUGCAUUGUCAAAGUCUGAGAAGGAUGUAUUGUACUUUGAAGGAAGACUUUCCAUUUCUAAGCUACCAUGGAGAAGUAUAUGCUCCUCGAGACCAGAGACUGUGACUUCUGCAUCUUUGAUUCCAGCGACAUAUGAUAAAAUGUUUUGCACAUAGUUGAAUCCAGCGUUGAUACAUGAAGGACAGCAUUACAUCUUUUUUCUAUUAUACUUAGAAAUUUCCUCUUUGUUCUGCACCACCAACCUGUAUAUCAAGCCUCCUUGCCCCACAAAGCUUCCAAAGCCCGUAAAUUUGUUAAUCUAGAGCAGGGGUCAGCAAACUACCACCCAUGGGCCAAAUCUGGCCUGCUGCCUAUUUUUGUAUGGCCUACAAACUAUGGUUUUUAUAUUCCCUUUUGUUAAUGGCUCAAAAUAAUAUUUUGUAUAAUACGAAAAUUACGAGAUUUUAGUUUCUCUAAAUAAAGUUUUGGAAAGAA